AUAUAAAUCUGUUCUGUGGAAGCCACCUGAAGUCAGGAAGAGAUGGAGGGCAUCCUUCAGGAGUGAGAUGAGACCUCAUCAUACUUGACUGUCCAGCAUCAUCUCUGAGCCUCAGCCUUUCCUGCCUUUGACUGAAACAGCAGUAUCUUCUAAGCCCUGGGGGCUUCCCCGGGCCCCAGCCCCGACCUAGAACCCGCCCGCUGCCUGCCACGCUGCCACUGCCGCUUCCUCUAUAAAGGGACCUGAGCGUCCGGGCCCAGGGGCUCCACACAGCAGGUGAGGCUCUCCUGCCCCAUCUCCUUGGGCUGCCCGUGCUUCGUGCUUUGGACUACCGCCCCGCAGUGUCCUGCCCUCUGCCUGGGCCUCGGUCCCUCCUGCACCUGCUGCCUGGAUCCCCGGCCUGCCUGGGCCUGGGCCUUGGUUCUCCCCAUGACACCACCUGAACGUCUCUUCCUCCCAAGGGUGUGUGGCACCACCCUACACCUCCUCCUUCUGGGGCUGCUGCUGGUUCUGCUGCCUGGGGCCCAGGGGCUCCCUGGUGUUGGCCUCACACCUUCAGCUGCCCAGACUGCCCGUCAGCACCCCAAGAUGCAUCUUGCCCACAGCAACCUCAAACCUGCUGCUCACCUCAUUGGAGACCCCAGCAAGCAGAACUCACUGCUCUGGAGAGCAAACACGGACCGUGCCUUCCUCCAGGAUGGUUUCUCCUUGAGCAACAAUUCUCUCCUGGUCCCCACCAGUGGCAUCUACUUCGUCUACUCCCAGGUGGUCUUCUCUGGGAAAGCCUACUCUCCCAAGGCCACCUCCUCCCCACUCUACCUGGCCCAUGAGGUCCAGCUCUUCUCCUCCCAGUACCCCUUCCAUGUGCCUCUCCUCAGCUCCCAGAAGAUGGUGUAUCCAGGGCUGCAGGAACCCUGGCUGCACUCGAUGUACCACGGGGCUGCGUUCCAGCUCACCCAGGGAGACCAGCUAUCCACCCACACAGAUGGCAUCCCCCACCUAGUCCUCAGCCCUAGUACUGUCUUCUUUGGAGCCUUCGCUCUGUAGAACUUGGAAAAAUCCAGAAAGAAAAAAUAAUUGAUUUCAAGACCUUCUCCCCAUUCUGCCUCCAUUCUGACCAUUUCAGGGGUCGUCACCACCUCUCCUUUGGCCAUUCCAACAGCUCAAGUCUUCCCUGAUCAAGUCACCGGAGCUUUCAAAGAAGGAAUUCUAGGCAUCCCAGGGGACCACACCUCCCUGAACCAUCCCUGAUGUCUGUCUGGCUGAGGAUUUCAAGCCUGCCUAGGAAUUCCCAGCCCAAAGCUGUUGGUCUGUCCCACCAGCUAGGUGGGGCCUAGAUCCACACACAGAGGAAGAGCAGGCACAUGGAGGAGCUUGGGGGAUGACUAGAGGCAGGGAGGGGACUAUUUAUGAAGGCAAAAAAAUUAAAUUAUUUAUUUAUGGAGGAUGGAGAGAGGGGAAUAAUAGAAGAACAUCCAAGGAGAAACAGAGACAGGCCCAAGAGAUGAAGAGUGAGAGGGCAUGCGCACAAGGCUGACCAAGAGAGAAAGAAGUAGGCAUGAGGGAUCACAGGGCCCCAGAAGGCAGGGAAAGGCUCUGAAAGCCAGCUGCCGACCAGAGCCCCACACGGAGGCAUCUGCACCCUCGAUGAAGCCCAAUAAACCUCUUUUCUCUGAAA